GUCCGUCCCGCUCGUUGGUGGCGCUGUUACAUAGCCCGUAGUCAGAGGCCUUUCAGCCCAGGGGCCGGCGCACGAAACCUGUUUGGAGGUUAUGGAUGAUAAACCCAAUCCUGAAGCCCUAAGUGACAGUUCAGAGCGUCUUUUCUCCUUUGGCGUCAUCGCAGAUGUUCAAUUUGCAGACUUAGAAGAUGGCUUUAAUUUCCAAGGAACCAGGCGGCGAUACUACAGACAUAGUCUUCUUCACUUACAGGGUGCCAUUGAAGACUGGAAUAAUGAAAGCAGCAUGCCCUGUUGUGUCCUUCAGCUUGGAGAUAUCAUCGAUGGAUAUAAUGCACAGUAUAAUGCAUCCAAAAAGUCCCUAGAACUUGUUAUGGACAUGUUCAAGAGGCUUAAAGUUCCAGUUCAUCAUACAUGGGGAAACCAUGAAUUCUAUAACUUCAGUAGAGAGUAUUUAACACACUCUAAACUUAACACUAAGUUUCUAGAAGAUCAGAUUGUACAUCAUCCUGAGACCAUGCCUUCAGAAGAUUAUUAUGCUUAUCAUUUUGUACCAUUCCCUAAAUUCCGGUUCAUUUUACUUGAUGCAUAUGACUUGAGUGUCUUGGGCGUGGAUCAGUCUUCUCCAAAAUACGAGCAGUGUAUGAAGAUAUUGAGGGAGCACAAUCCAAAUACGGAACUGAAUAGUCCUCAAGGACUUUCUGAGCCCCAGUUUGUCCAGUUUAAUGGAGGAUUCAGCCAAGAACAGCUAAACUGGUUGAAUGAAGUGCUAACAUUCUCUGACACAAACCAAGAAAAGGUGGUGAUUGUGAGCCAUCUUCCCAUUUACCCGGACGCCUCUGACAAUGUGUGCCUGGCCUGGAACUACAGAGAUGCCCUGGCAGUCAUUUGGUCUCAUGAGUGUGUGGUGUGUUUCUUUGCUGGUCACACCCAUGAUGGUGGCUACUCUGAGGAUCCUUUUGGUGUAUACCACGUCAACCUAGAAGGAGUUAUUGAAACAGCUCCAGACAGCCAAGCCUUUGGCACAGUUCAUGUCUAUCCUGACAAAAUGAUGUUGAAAGGGAGAGGCAGAGUUCCAGAUAGAAUUAUGAAUUACAAGAAAGAAAGAGCCUUCCAUUGUUAGUCUAAUUUAUUUUAACUUGAUAGAAAAUGAGCUUUGUGUUUGUCCCUCCUAAACAAAAAAAUAAAAAUCCUCUGUCUCAUUGUUUAGUAUUCAGCUUGCAUAACAAAAUGUAUUUAUAGUUUCAGUGUGUGAUGGUUGAUAAAAUACUCAGAAAUGUUAUUUUGGAUCAUGUAUCCAUUGUAAGUUAGAAACAAACCAGGGAGGAAACUGAGGCAGGGGUGUAUAGUCCUCAUAAGGGGCAUAUAGUCCUCAUGAGGGAUCUUAUUUGGCCCUACCUGAUUUUUUUUAACUUUUUACAAGGAGAUUGUAUUCACAUGUGUUAACUAUGUAACUUCAAGUUCAGCAUAUAAGCUCAGGUAAGCUUUUUCUAUUCACCCUGCUGUGUAAAUGAGCUUUGGACAAUUUCUGCUCAGA